ACUUCUGGCGGCGCCCUCAUGGUUGCGUUAGCAUGGCUACCUAGGGAUCUGUUCACUGAUUUAGAGGGUCCCAGAGCUCUGGGUCGGGACUGAGGUGAAAGAGCGGAAAAACGCGAGAAGCGGUGUUCCUUCUACACAGAGGCUAGAGUGCGGAUCGGCUGAGUCGGCUGCAGGCGCCCCUGCCUCCGUCAGCGUCCAGGUGACCGCCGUUCCCGCCCCGCUCUUCCCUGGGUGGACUGGAGGAGGCCGCGCCGAUGAACCUGACCGAGGUGCGUGCAGCGUCCCAGGCCGCCCCGCCCAACCCCUCCUCCCAGUGCUGAAGUCCCAAGGAGCCGCCCUGCAGGAUUGUAUGGUCUUUGAGGAUGUGGCCAUAUAUUUCUCCCAAGAGGAAUGGGGGAUCCUUAAUGAUGCUCAGAGACACCUGCACAGCAAUGUGAUGUUGGAGAACUUUGCGCUUUUGUCAUCAGUAGGUUGUUGGCAUGGAGCCAAGGAUGAGGAGGUACCUUCCAAGCAGUGUGUUUCUGUAAGAGUGUUACAGGUCACAAUUCCAAAGCCAGCUUUGUCCACCCUGAAGGCCCAGCCCUGCAAGAUGUGUAGCUCAAUUCUGAAGGACAUUCUGCACCUGGCUGAGCACGAUGGAACACACCCUGAGCAAGGGCUGUACACAUGUGCAGCAGAGCAUGACCUGCACCAAAAGGAGCAGAUUAGAGAGAAGCUCACCAGAAGUGAUGAGUGGAGGCCUUCAUUUGUGAACCACAGUGCUCACGUGGGAGAGAGGAACUUCACAUGCACGCAGGGUGGCAAGGAUUUUACUGCCAGCUCAGACCUUCUCCAGCAACAGGUCUUAAACAGUGGGUGGAAGCUGUACAGGGAUACCCAGGAUGGGGAAGCCUUUCAAGGUGAACAGAAUGAUUUCAACUCCAGCCAAGGUGGGAAAGACUUUUGCCACCAACAUGGGCUGUUUGAGCACCAAAAAACCCAUAAUGGGGAGAGGCCUUAUGAGUUCAGUGAAUGUGGGGAAUUGUUUAGGUACAACUCCAACCUUAUUAAAUAUCAGCAAAAUCAUGCUGGAGAAAGGCCUUAUGAGGGCACUGAAUAUGGAAAGACCUUUAUUAGAAAGUCCAACCUAGUUCAGCACCAGAAAAUUCACAGUGAAGGCUUUCUUUCAAAAAGGUCUGACCCCAUUGAACAUCAGGAGAUUCUCAGUAGACCAACACCUUAUGAAUGCACCCAGUGUGGGAAGGCCUUUCUUACACAGGCUCAUCUGGUUGGUCACCAGAAAACCCAUACUGGAGAACAGCCCUAUGAAUGCAACAAGUGUGGGAAGUUUUUUAUGUAUAACUCCAAACUCAUCAGACAUCAGAAAGUUCACACUGGGGAGAGGCGUUACGAGUGCAGUGAAUGUGGGAAAUUGUUUAUGGACAGCUUCACACUCGGUAGACAUCAGAGAGUUCAUACUGGAGAAAGGCCUUUUGAAUGCAGCAUAUGUGGAAAAUUCUUUAGUCACCGCUCCACACUCAAUAUGCACCAGAGAGUUCAUGCUGGCAAAAGGCUUUAUAAGUGUAGCGAAUGUGGGAAAGCCUUUAGCCUCAAACAUAAUGUUGUUCAGCAUCUGAAAAUUCAUACUGGAGAACGGCCUUAUGAGUGCACUGAAUGUGAGAAGGCCUUUGUUAGAAAGUCCCACCUAGUUCAGCACCAGAAAAUCCACACUGAUGCAUUUUCAAAAAGGUCUGACCUCAUUCAACACAAGAGGAUUGACAUUAGGCCAAGGCCUUAUACAUGCAGUGAAUGUGGGAAGGCCUUCCUUACACAGGCUCAUCUGGUUGGUCACCAGAAAAUCCAUACUGGAGAACGGCCUUAUGAAUGCACUCAAUGUGCGAAGGCCUUUGUUAGAAAGUCCCACCUAGUUCAGCAUGAGAAAAUCCACACUGAUGCAUUUUCAAAAAGGUCUGACCUCAUUCAACACAAGAGGAUUGACCUCAGGCCAAGGCCUUAUGUGUGUAGUGAAUGUGGGAAGGCCUUCCUUACACAGGCUCAUCUAGAUGGUCACCAGAAAAUCCAGACUGGAGAACGGCGUUAUGAAUGCAAUGAAUGUGGGAAAUUCUUUUUGGACAGCUACAAACUUGUUAUUCAUCAGAGAAUUCACACUGGAGAAAAGCCUUAUAAAUGCAGCAAAUGUGGGAAAUUCUUUAGAUAUCGCUGUACACUGAGUAGACAUCAGAAAGUUCACACUGGAGAAAGACCUUAUGAGUGUAGUGAAUGUGGGAAAUUUUUUAGAGAUAGCUACAAACUCAUUAUUCAUCAGAGAGUUCAUACUGGAGAAAAGCCUUAUGAAUGCAGCAACUGUGGGAAGUUUCUUAGAUACCGCUCUACAUUCAUUAAACAUCAUAAAGUUUGCACUGGGGAGAAGCCUCAUGAGUGCAGUAAAUGUAGGGAAUUGUUUAGGACUAAAUCGAGCCUUAUUAUACAUCAGCAGUCUCACACUGGAGAAAGUCCUUUUAAGUUAAGGGAAUGUGGGAAAGACUUCAACAAAUGUAAUACUGGUCAGCGCCAAAAAACUCACACUGGAGAAAGGUCUUAUGAGUGUGGUGAAUCCAGCAAAGUGUUUAAAUACAACUCCAGCCUCAUUAAACAUCAGAUAAUUCAUACUGGAAAAAGGCCUUAGUGGAGUGAAUGCAGGAAAGUCACCAAAACUGUCACCUCAUUCAGCACCAAAAGGUUCACAUCGGACCAAGAACCUAUUAAUAUAUGUAAAUCUAAUGUUGAAAGAGUUCAGAUGGAAAUCUGCGAGGAUUUCCUGCUGGGAACUACAUUAAAAACAUUUAUGUCCAGGCGUGGUGGCUCACGCCUGUAAUCCCAGCACUUUGGGAGGCAGAGGUGGGUGGAUCACCUGAGGUCAGGAGUUUGAGACCAGCCGGGCCAACAUGGUGAAGCCCCAUCUCUACUAAAAAUACAAAAAUUAGCUGGGCAUGGUGGCAGGUGCCUGUAAUCCCAGCUAUUCAGGGGACUGAGGCAGGGAGCAUCACUUGAACCUGGGAGGCGGAGGUUGCAGUGAACUGAGAUUGUUCCAUUGCACUCCAGCCUGGGUGACAGGGCGAGACUCUGUCUCAAAAAGAAAAAAAUUAUAAUUGUGGCAAAUUACAGGUAACUUAAAAUCUACCAUCUUAACCCAUAUUUAACUGUACUGUUCAGUAGUGUUAAGUCAUUCGCAUUGUUGUCAAUUAAUAUCCAGAAGUUUUUUCAACUUAAUGAAACUAAAACAUUAUACCCUUUAAACCAGGGGUCCACAACCCCCAGGCUGCAAACUGGUACCAGUCUGUGGCCUGUUAGGAACCGGGCCAGCAUCACUACCUGAGCUUCACCUCCUGUCAGAUGAGCAGCAUUAGAUUCUCAUAGCAGCCUGAGCCCUAUUGUGAACUGUGCCUGUGAGGGAUCUAGGUUGUGUGCUCCUUAUGAGAAUCUAACUAAUACCUGAUGAUCUGAGGUGGGACAGUUUUAUUCUGAAACUGUCUGCCCCCUCCUCUGUCCCUGAUGCGUGGAAAAAUUGGCUUCCAUGAAACCAGUCCCUGGUGCCAAAGAGGUUGGGGACCGCUGCUUUAAACUACUCCUCUUCCUCAUUCCCUACGCCAACCAGCCCCUGACAAUACUACUGUAUGAAUUUUACUAUAAAUAUCUCAUAUGAGGAAACUUAAGUUUUAGUCUUUUGUGACUUAUUUUGAGGCUUAUUUCCCUAAAUGUCUUCAAGGUUUAUCCAUGUUGUAGCAUAGCUUAUGAUUUUCAUCUUUUUUAAAGGCCGAAUAAAAUCCCAUUGUAGUCAUGUGUCGCCUAACAAGAGGACUGUGUUCUGAGUAAUCAUCUUAAGGUGAUUUUGUCAUUGUGUGAACAAAGAGUGUACUUACACAAACCUGAAGGGCACAGCCUAUUACGCACCUAGGCUAUAUGAUAUGGUCCAUUGCGCCUCAGAUAUAAACCUUAACAGCAUGUUACAGUAUUGAAUAUUGUAGGUAAUUGAAACACAAUGAUAAGUAAAUGUGUAUCUAAACAUAUCUAAGUUUCCAAAAGGUACUGUAAAAAUGUAUGAAAAAUGGUAAAAACUUUAUAGGGCACUAACAUGAACGAAGCUUGCGGGACCCCUCUGGUUGAGUCAGGGAGUGAGUUGUGAGUGAAUGUGAAGCUCUAGGACAUUACUGUACCCUAUUGUAGAUGUUAUAAACAUUGUACACUUAGGCUACUCUAAAUUAAUUUUUUCUUUAGUAAUAAAUUAACCUUAGUCUACUGUAA